GGUUCCGCGUUCUGGUUCCGCCAUGGAAUCCAACAAGGAUGAAGCUGAGCGCUGUAUCAGCAUCGCCCUCAAGGCCAUCCAGAGCAACCAGCCCGACCGGGCGCUCCGCUUCCUGGAGAAGGCACAGCGGCUGUAUCCGACGCCGCGAGUUCGCGCCCUGAUUGAGUCCCUCAACCAGAAACCACAGACUGCCGGUGACCAACCCCCACCCACAGACACAACCCAUGCCACCCACAGGAAAGCAGGUGGGACCGAUGCCCCCUCGGCCAACGGUGAAGCUGGAGGAGAGAGCACCAAAGGCUACACUGCAGAACAGGUUGCAGCUGUGAAAAGGGUCAAGCAAUGUAAAGAUUACUAUGAGAUCCUGGGGGUGAGCAGAGGGGCCUCGGAUGAGGACCUGAAGAAGGCCUACCGCAGACUGGCCCUCAAAUUCCACCCAGACAAGAACCACGCACCUGGUGCCACUGAAGCCUUCAAAGCCAUUGGCACAGCAUAUGCGGUACUCAGCAACCCGGAGAAGAGGAAGCAGUAUGACCAGUUCGGCGAUGACAAGAGCCAGGCGGCCCGGCACGGCCAUGGGCAUGGGGAUUUCCACCGUGGCUUUGAGGCCGACAUCUCCCCUGAAGACCUCUUCAACAUGUUCUUUGGCGGCGGCUUCCCUUCUAGUAACGUCCACGUCUACAGCAACGGCCGCAUGCGCUAUACCUACCAGCAAAGGCAGGACCGCAGGGACAACCAGGGUGAUGGCGGGCUAGGGGUGUUUGUGCAGCUGAUGCCUAUCCUCAUCCUGAUUCUCGUGUCAGCUCUCAGCCAGCUCAUGGUCUCCAGUCCACCCUACAGUCUGAGUCCAAGACCGUCCGUGGGCCACAUCCACAGGCGAGUCACUGACCACCUGGGUGUCGUCUACUAUGUGGGAGACACUUUCUCCGAAGAGUACACAGGCUCCAGCCUCAAAACAGUCGAGCGGAAUGUGGAAGAUGAUUAUAUCGCCAACCUCCGGAACAACUGCUGGAAGGAGAAGCAGCAGAAGGAAGGCUUGCUGUACCGGGCACGCUACUUUGGCGACACAGAUAUGUACCACAGAGCACAGAAGAUGGGCACCCCCAGCUGCAGCCGACUGUCAGAGGUGCAGGCCUCCCUGCAUGGAUAGUCCUGGGCCAGCCACACCACCGAGGUCCAAGUAUGAGCCAGGGCUGCCUCCACCCUGCAACUCCUGGCAGCUUUGGCCCUGGUCAUGAGCAGAGGAGGGAGGGGGAGAAAGGGAGGAAGCCUGGUGAUUGUGGCAAAGACUCCUGUCCCCAGCCUGACCUCCAGCCUCCAGAGACCGAGCAGCUGUGGGGCCUGCUGGGAAACCAAGGUCGGUUUCCGCCCUCUAGCGAUGCUGUCCUCCCCACUCCUCCGCUCUGCUCCCUGGCUCCAGGGGUGUGGGGGACCCCAGAACCAGGCAGAGUGGGAACUUGAAACUGUUGCUGAGGGCCACCCGGGGCUUCUUGGUCCACUCCAGCCAUCAGUCAGCACGGCCCUUUCUCCAGCACAGCAGACUAUUGUCCGUGCCCUGGUAUUUAGGCCAUCACAUAUGGUGGGGCCCAAGAGAGCCCCAUAUGCACACUGCCUGCCUGAUACCAGGAAGAACCAUGUGGGAAUAGGUGGGCCAAGAGCCCUCCCCUUUCUCCAUCCCUCCAGCUAGGAGGAAAUGGAGCAAGAUGAACAGGCAGCCACGAGGUGGGUGGGAGCUGGCAGUCUUGGUGGCGGCAGGGGCCGCGGGCCCUGACCACCCCCCUCUGGUGGGAUCUGAGGCACUCUCUCGAAUGCCGUCACACCUGGCAGCCUGGAAGCCACAGGCAUCCGGCCUUGCCCAGGCAUCUCGCCUGCGGUCUGAGGAAGGGAACAGAAGGUCAUGAGUUCAGGGUCAGACGCAGCCGCUCAGCACAGGAGGGGUGGAGGGGAAAUGAGAGUUGCUGGUAGCAGGCUCCCUCCUUCUGCAGCCCGGCGAAUGGGGGCGCUGGGCUCUGUUCCCAGCGUUUGCCAGAGGUGGCCACUUCAGCCAAGCCCAGAGAAGUGUGGGCAGAAGCAGUGAAGGUUCUUCUCUGUGUGGGUGCCCUGCCCACCCCCUCCUUUGCCUGUGUCCUCCCGGCCUGGAUCCAUGGCUGACUCUGCCUGGAGGCCAUUUGUGCCUGCCUCUGUGCUGCCGCAGGAGGGCAGGCCGCAAGUGGGGUUGGUGGGGGUCGAGCGGGCAGCACGGUGCAGCGGUGCAGUGGCAAGGGGGGCUACUUGUGUGGCAUAAGCUAGAGGAGCCGGUGCCGCCUGAAUGCCGAGCUAACUGUUGCCACUCUCCUCCCCAGACUAUGAAAUCCCUGGAGAAUUUUUGGUGACAUGCACUGAGCCAAGGUGAUGGACUGUAUAUUUGAGGAAAGACAAACAAAGAAACAAAAUUAAAAUGGAAUUGGAGGCCGAACGCUGCACAGCUGCCCUCUCUCUCACCCAGUAAAUGCAGAAAGCUCUUAGGACAGACAGAAAACCUGCCAUGGGGCUGCUUCCCUCCCUCGCAGGGCUGGCGGAGGCUCCGCAUCGCCUCUCUCCUAGGAUACAGAAACCAUGGCAACGAAAGUAGAAUGUAAAACUCGCAGCAGAUAUCAGUGGGAAGGGCUGGGGGAGGGGGCACCCAGCUGCCUUUCCUCCCUCACAGGAGCCACCACCAGCCACCUCUCAGGAGAAGCCAGAGGCCCUGGCCAAAGAUAGGAGGAAGAAAGAGAACUCUCCAUAGAAUGUAAUUUAUAGAUGCGUGUAUAUGUAUAUAUAUCUAUUUAUAUGUAAAUAGGCAUAUAUGAAGAUAUAUAUAUAUAUAGUCUACUUUUUAAACUCUGCAGGGAUUUGGUUAAGUUGUUGAGCUGAUUUCUUCCAUGUUUUAGAAAAUGAGGCCUGUUUGGGGAAGGUACCCUGGUGAUGUUUUUGCUAGACAUUAGCUGUAGCUGACAGCAUAAGGAGAGUCGCAUCAGAGCUUUUCACAGCCCCCCGAAACCCCAGCCUGGUUUUGAUGGCAGCAGUAAUCAUGAUAGUGUGAACCCGCGAAGGCCUCAGGAUUAUGGUUAACCUGGAGAGGAGCAGGCCAUGGAGGCAGGUGCCAGGUCAGUAUUGAGUCACAGUAGAGGCCCCACAAGGACCUGCUUGGGUGAGACCACCUCUCCCCUCUCAGCAGCGCUGGUGGGCUCUUUGUCCUGGUGCCCAGGAGCCCUCCAGCCCCCUGCCCACAGAAGGGAAGGCCUGCAGAGGGGGCCAGGAUCUACCUAACCAUUUCCCCACCCCUAAGUCCCUCAGUGGGCUUUGCCUUAUAGGUGCCACAGGGCACAGCUCCAUCAUUGCCACUGGUUUUUCCUAAGUCAUGCACCAAGGACUUCAGAAAGUUCUUCCUCCGAGUCAGUCAGUGGUGCCGGGACCCCAGGGCAGCCUCCUCGACUCCUGAAGAAAAGGCAGUGCCCGUGGCUGCCUCUGUCUUCACUCGCUGUUGAUGUGACCGCCAGGCCUCCUCUCGUACCUUGGACAAAGGAUACACCUGAACCAGAAUAGUUUUCUUACCCUCACAUUGAAAUGAGGAUUUUGCUUAAAACAGCACUUGCCGCCAGUGGGAGGAGGGAGGUUUUAUUUAUUCCCACAGUUUCUCCUGGGCCUUCUGGAAUGACCAUGUUUUCCUGUGGCGGUGGGUGUGUCAUUGCGCCCGCCGUCUUCCAAAGCCUUACUUCCCCAAGCUGCCAGCCAGGAGGUGAUAACCACCCUCCCAGAGUUUCUCUCGGCUCUUUUUUUAAAAGUCCCCCAACAAAUAGGAUUCUUGCUGGGAAAGGAAGUUCGGUAAGGAAAUGUCAAAUCUGGUUUUUAAACAAGGUCCAACCCUGCAAUGAAGCAGCCACUUCAGCCCAGAGAGAUUAUAAGAACUGAUGUGGCCAGAGUGCCUACCCACUGUGGCCCCGGUGCUCUGCCCCCACGCCCCGACCAUCUGGUCUUGGUAGAUGUCCCUAGACGGGCUGAGCCAUGUGCAAUAAGAACAUAGAUCCUAAAGGAUCCUCUGGAAGCUGUAUUUCUUGAAUUAGAAUUCUCAAAUUGUA